ACACUCUUCGUCAUCACCUCUCCUAUUCGCCUGGACAAGCUCAUGUUUGCAGGAGCACCAUGUCUUGCUCGUCUCGCGCCUCCUCCUCCAGGGCUGGAGGCAGCAGCUCAGCCAGGGUGUCUGCUGGUGGAAGCAGCUUCAGCAGUGGAAGCAGAUGUGGUCUGGGGGGCAGCUCGGCCCAGGGCUUCCGAGGAGGAGCCAGCAGCUGCAGCCUGAGUGGGGGGUCUAGCGGUGCUUUUGGGGGCAGCUUUGGAGGGGGCUUUGGUAGCUGCUCAGUAGGGGGUGGUUUUGGGGGAGCUUCAGGCUCUGGGACAGGAUUUGGUGGGGGUUCUAGCUUUGGCGGGGUCUCUGGAUUUGGCAGGGGUUCUGGAUUCUGUGGGAGUUCUAGAUUCAGCAGUGGUGCUACUGGAGGCUUCUACAGCUAUGGUGGUGGUAUGGGAGGUGGUGUUGGCGAUGGGGGGCUUUUCUCUGGAGGGGAAAAGCAAACCAUGCAGAACCUCAAUGACCGCUUGGCCAAUUACCUAGACAAGGUCAGAGCCCUGGAGGAGGCUAACACUGAUCUGGAGAACAAAAUCAAGGAGUGGUAUGACAAAUAUGGGCCUGGGUCUGGAGACGGUGGAUCGGGAAGAGAUUAUAGCAAAUACUAUUCAAUAAUUGAAGAUCUCAGAAACCAGAUCAUUGCUGCCACUGUUGAAAAUGCUGGGAUCAUUUUGCACAUUGACAAUGCCAGAUUGGCUGCUGAUGACUUCAGACUGAAGUAUGAGAACGAGCUGUGUCUCCGGCAGAGCGUGGAGGCUGACAUCAAUGGCCUGCGGAAAGUCCUGGAUGACCUGACUAUGACCCGCUCUGACCUGGAGAUGCAGAUUGAGAGUUUCACCGAGGAGCUAGCCUACCUGAGGAAGAACCACGAGGAGGAAAUGAAGAAUAUGCAAGGAAGCUCUGGAGGGGAGGUGACCGUAGAAAUGAAUGCUGCGCCAGGGACCGACCUGACCAAAUUACUGAAUGACAUGAGGGCGCAGUACGAGGAGCUGGCUGAGCAAAACCGCCGAGAGGCUGAGGAGCGGUUCAACAAGCAGAGCGCAUCACUACAAGCACAAAUCUCCACUGAUGCUGGGGCAGCCACUUCUGCCAAGAAUGAGAUAACAGAACUAAAACGUACCCUGCAAGCCCUGGAAAUUGAGCUUCAGUCCCAACUGGCCAUGAAAAGCUCCCUGGAGGGAACCCUGGCUGACACAGAAGCUGGCUACGUGGCUCAGCUGUCAGAAAUUCAAACGCAGAUCAGUGCCCUGGAGGAGGAGAUCUGCCAGAUCUGGGGUGAGACUAAAUGCCAGAACGCAGAGUACAAGCAAUUGCUGGACAUCAAGACACGCCUGGAGGUGGAGAUCGAGACCUACCGCCGCCUGCUCGAUGGAGAGGGAGGUGGUUCUAGUUUUGCAGAAUUUGGUGGUAGAAACUCAGGAUCUGUAAACAUGGGAUCCAGGGAUCUGGUAUCUGGUGACUCAAGAUCUGGAAGCUGUUCUGGUCAAGGACGAGAUUCAAGCAAGACUAGAGUGACUAAGACUAUCGUAGAGGAGUUGGUGGAUGGCAAGGUUGUCUCGUCUCAAGUCAGCAGUAUUUCUGAGGUGAAAGUUAAAUAAGGAACUUCCAGAUCAACAAAAGUGUCUUUCAAAGAAAAAAAAAUCAAGAAGGACACAAGCGAAGAAAUGGCAUCAAUCUAGGCAUCUUUCUGGAUAAUUUCAGGAAAAGCUUCAGUCCAGAAAUGGAUGACUAGCCAACUUUUCUGCAUCUUCUUAUUUCCUCAUUAGAAUGCUCUUGAAAUAGCUGAAUUAACAACUUUGCUUUAAUUGUUUCUAUGCUUCAAUAAAUUUACUUUUGCAAGUUAA